AUGUCGCUCAUGGUCGUCAGCAUGGCGUGUGUUGGGUUCUUCUUGCUGCAGGGGGCCUGGACACAUGAGGGUGGUCAGGACAAGCCCUUCCUCUCUGCCUGGCCCAGCCCUGUGGUGUCUGAAGGAGAACAUGUGGCUCUUCAGUGUCGCUCUCGUCUUGGGUUUAACGAAUUCAGUCUGUCCAAAGAAGACGGGAUGCCUGUCCCUGAGCUCUACAACAGAGUAUUCCGAAACACCGUUUUCAUAGGCCCUGUGACCCCAGCACAUGCAGGGACCUACAGAUGUCGGGGUUCACACCCACACUUCCUCACUGGGUGGUCAGCACCCAGCAACCCCCUGGUGAUCAUGGUCACAGGAGUCCACAGAAAACCUUCCCUCCUGGCCCACCCAGGUCCCCUGGUGAAAUCAGAAGAGACAGUCAUCCUGCAAUGUUGGUCAGAUGUCAUGUUUGAGCACUUCCUUCUGCACAGAGAGGGGAAGUUUAAUGACACUUUGCGCCUCACUGGAGAGCUCCAUGAUGGGGUCUCCAAGGCCAACUUCUCCAUCGGUCGCAUGACGCAAGACCUUGCAGGGACCUACAGAUGCUACGGUUCUGUUCCUCAUUCCCCCUAUCAGUUGUCAGCUCCCAGUGACCCUCUGGACAUCGUGAUUACAGGUCUAUGUGGGAAACCUUCUCUCUCAGCCCAGCCGCGCCCCAUGGUUAAGGCAGGAGAGAGCGUGACCUUGUCCUGCAGCUCCCGGAGCUCCUAUGACAUCUACCAUCUAUCAAGGGAGGGGGAGGCUCAUGAACUUAGGUUCCCUGCAGUGCCCAAGGUCAAUGGAACCUUCCAGGCCAACUUUCCUCUGGGCCCUGCCACCCACGGAGGGACCUACAGAUGCUUCGGCUCUUUCCGUGACUCUCCCUACGAGUGGUCAGACCUUAGUGACCCACUGCUUGUUUCUGUCACAGAUGUUUUUUGCUCUCUCCACACCUUGGAGACUCAGUGGGGGAGUCUUCUCUGGGGACUCGGGGAGGGCCUCCCUGGGACUCGCAGGAUUUCCAAGCUAGAUGACAACAUGACAGGUGGAAACAGGCCCAUUCCUUCGCCAGGGGCCCCAAGCUCCAUCCCAGGAGAUGAGAAGAGGCUCUUCUCAUUGAAAGAAUGUGUGGCUUGUCUGCUCUCCAGCCCUGUCAUGGAGAUUGAUAAUCCUUAG